AGAUAUGCAGCCGGUUUCCCCUGAGGGGUCUCGGAGUCCGGAACCCCCAACCCAAAUCUGGAGGAUGAGGAACCCGGAGUCUGCAUUUCUUAGUAUCCGAGAAGGAGGGGCCUGAAUUCCAGAACUCCUGGGUCUGAGAGAGGAGGGCACUGGGGGCCUGGAUUCCUGGGUCUGAGGGAGAAGGGCGCUGGGGGCAUGGACUCCUGGGUCUGAAGGAGGAGGGCGCUGGGGACCUGGACUCCAGGGUCUGAGGGAGAAGGGUGCUGGGGGCCUGGGCCUGGACUCCUCCUGGGUCUGAGGGAGAAGGGUGCUGGGGGCCUGGACUUCUGGGUCUGAGAGAGGAGGGCGCUGGGGGCCUGGACUACUCCUGGGUCUGAGGGAGGAGGGCGCUGGGGAUCUGAACUCCUGGGUCUGAAGGUGGAGGCCCUGGGGUCUGCACUACUCGGUCUGAGGGAGAAGGCGGUCCUGGUUGGGUCAGCCUGGGCUCCUUUCACUCUCCACCCUUCCCCUUUCCUGUACCGAGGAGCCAGGGCAGGCAGCCACUCCAGGUAUGUGCAGAAGUCUUGGGCGGGCCCUGGCCUGUCCUGUGAGGAGGGAACAUUCCAGGAAGCAGCUUGGGGAACCAGGGCUUCUUGAGUGUGGGCCCUCAGGGACCCGGGUGUCCAGGCCAGUUCCGCCCCAUCUGGGAGAUGAAUGGGCCGAGGGGGAUGUAAUCUCUUCCAGCCUCCUUCAUCCACUGCCUCUCCCUUCCCCUAUUCUCCCUUCCCCUCCCUCCAUCUGCUUCCCAUCCCAGCCAGGAGCCAUCACCUGGGUAGAAAAGGGGCCUCUGGAAAGGGGGCGGGGCCUUGACUCUUGGGUACCCUGCACUUGAAGAGGAACUCUGGGAAGGGGUUGUUCAGGGAUUUGGCCCCUUCCCCACCUGCCUCUAUAACCUGUCUAUUCUUUUCUUCCCCUAGGUGGUUGCCCCCUCCCUCUCCUGAGAUGUCAGGAAGGAGGGGGCCACCUGUGUCCUCCACAGGGGCCCCCCGAAGCCUGGGGACUCCCAGCCCCAGAGCUCCGAGGCGGAGGAGGUGCUGACAGGUCUGGUGCUCCGAGAGAUGCUCCCUCUCCCCUCAUGCUCCCUCCCCAUCCUCCUCCUUUUCCUCCUCCCCAGUGUGCCAAUUGAGUCCCAACCCCCACCCUCAACAUUGCCCCCUUUUCUGGCCCCUGAGUGGGACCUUCUCUCCCCCCGAGUAGUCCUGUCUAGGGGUGCCCCUGCUGGGCCCCCUCUGCUCUUCCUGCUGGAGGCUGGGGCCUUUCGGGAGUCAGCAGGUGCCCCGGCCAACCGCAGCCGGCGUGGGGUGAGCGAAACUGCACCAGCGAGUCGUCGGGGUGAGCUGGCUGUGUGCGAUGCAGUCAGUGGCUGGGUGACAGACCGCCGGACCGCUGUGGACUUGCGUGGGCGCGAGGUGGAGGUGUUGGGCGAGGUGCCUGCAGCUGGCGGCAGUCCCCUCCGCCAGUACUUCUUUGAAACCCGCUGCAAGGCUGAUAACGCUGAGGAAGGUGGCCCGGGGGCAGGUGGAGGGGGCUGCCGGGGAGUGGACAGGAGGCACUGGGUAUCUGAGUGCAAGGCCAAGCAGUCCUAUGUGCGGGCAUUGACCGCUGAUGCCCAGGGCCGUGUGGGCUGGCGAUGGAUUCGAAUUGACACUGCCUGCGUCUGCACACUCCUCAGCCGGACUGGCCGGGCCUGAGACCCAUGCCCAGGAAAAUAACAGAGCUGGAUGCUGAGAGACCUCAGGGAUGGCCCAGCUGAUCUAAGGACCCCAGUUUGGGAACUCAUCAAAUAAUCACAAAAUCACAAUUCUCUGAUUUUGAGCUCAAUCUCUGCAGGAUGGGUGAAACCACAUGGGGUUUUGGAGGUUGAAUAGGAGUUCUCCUGGAGCAACUUGAGGGUAAUAAUGAUGAUGAUAUAAUAAUAAUAGCCACUA